AGUCACCCUUGGUGCCCUGUACUUCACUGUGGUCCUGAACUGAAGAGCUGUGUUUUUCAGGAAGACUUGGCCAGGCCGUGUUCCGUGUCUCUGGAUUCAAGUCCCAGGAGUCCUGACCAGAGAGCAGGCAUCAGUGUUUUUCUGACCGAAGUUCUCAUUUCCUGACAAUGGAAAUGGAACAAGAAAAAAUGACCAUGAAUAAGGAAUUGAGUCCAGACGCGGCUGCUUACUGCUGCUCGGCCUGCCACGGCGAUGAGACCUGGAGUUACAACCACCCCAUCCGGGGCCGGGCCAAGUCUCGCAGCCUGUCUGCCUCGCCCGCCCUGGGGAGCACCAAGGAGUUCAGGAGGACACGCUCUCUUCAUGGGCCAUGCCCGGUGACCACUUUUGGACCAAAGGCCUGUGUGCUGCAGAACCCCCAGACCAUCAUAGCCACUCCUUUGUCACUCGCAUCUCAGCUGCUGCCUUCACCAGCCGUCAGUCACUCGGGCCAGGGCGGGGUCACCGGACAGGUGCAUGUUCUGCCUCAGCCCUCAGACCAGGGCGUACUCAGUGGUCCCCGAGCUGCCCGAGGCCAGACAGCCCCGCAGGAGGAAGCGGUGACCCAGGAAGAGGUCGAGGCGCUGGUUUGUGGUCACACACAGCGGUGGGUGCCUGGGCCGGUGUACGACGCCGCUGCUGGUGGCUCUGGCUGGGCUCAGCUGAGCCUCAGGGCUGGAAUGGGUGUAGGCCAGGCCACUGGGCACAUUCAGGACCCCGCGAGCCAGCGGCUGACGUGGAACAAGUCCCCAAAGAGCGUCCUUGUCAUCAAGAAGAUGAGAGAUGCCAGCCUACUGCAGCCGUUCAAGGAGCUCUGCACGCACCUCAUGGAGGCACGCGGGGCAGGGGGGAAGGGGGCCUGGGGUGCACAUGGAGUUGGGGGGGCCUCCAUCCACAUCACCGCCCCGAGGGUGGGGUCUGCAGGUGGAAUGAGCAGGUUGGCACUUUGCUUCCAGGAGAACAUGAUCGUGUAUGUGGAAAAGAAAGUGCUAGAAGACCCUGCCAUCGCCAGCGAUGAAAGCUUUGGGGCAGUGAAGAAGAAAUUCUGUACCUUUCGAGAAGAUUAUGAUGACAUUUCCAAUCAGAUAGACUUCAUCAUCUGCCUGGGGGGAGACGGGACGCUGCUGUACGCUUCCUCGCUUUUCCAGGGCAGCGUCCCUCCGGUCAUGGCCUUCCACCUGGGCUCCCUGGGCUUCCUGACCCCAUUCAGCUUUGAGAACUUUCAGUCCCAAGUUACUCAGGUGAUAGAGGGGAACGCAGCUGUUGUUCUCCGGAGUCGGCUGAAGGUCAGGGUGGUGAAGGAGCUCCGGGGGAAGAAGACGGCCGUGCACAAUGGGCUGGGUGAGAACGGCUCGCAGGCUGCAGGCCUGGACAUGGAUGUCGGGAAGCAGGCCAUGCAGUACCAGGUCCUGAAUGAGGUGGUGAUUGACAGAGGCCCCUCCUCCUACCUGUCCAAUGUGGAUGUCUACCUGGACGGACACCUCAUCACCACGGUGCAGGGCGACGGAGUGAUCGUGUCCACCCCGACGGGCAGCACGGCGUAUGCGGCCGCGGCCGGGGCCUCCAUGAUCCACCCCAACGUGCCGGCCAUCAUGAUCACGCCCAUCUGCCCCCACUCGCUGUCCUUCCGGCCCAUCGUGGUCCCCGCAGGGGUCGAGCUGAAGAUCAUGCUGUCACCUGAAGCAAGGAACACAGCAUGGGUGUCCUUUGAUGGACGGAAGAGACAAGAGAUCCGCCAUGGAGACAGCAUCAGCAUCACUACCUCAUGCUACCCGCUCCCCUCCAUCUGUGUGCGGGACCCCGUGAGCGACUGGUUUGAGAGCCUCGCCCAGUGCCUGCAUUGGAACGUCCGGAAGAAGCAAGCCCACUUCGAGGAGGAGGAGGAGGAGGAGGAGGAGGGCUAGGUCAAGCCCCUAUCCAGGCCCGAAUCCUUCCGCUGCCCUCCAAGCGCCCUCUGGGGACAGACCAAUCUGCGUGUGUCUGUGACCGCCUGUCUCAGUGGCACGGCCACUUCCUUUCUGUAGCUGGGUUAGAGCCUGGGUCUGCCUUUUGUCCAGAUCAGCUGUUUUUUUAAAAUGUCUGACUUUUUUUGCAUUUCUAAAGAAGCGUGAGAAAUGGGCUGGGAGUGCUUCUGUCCUGCUGACACCCCGCGGUGGGUCCCUGGAGCGCGGCCUCCAGCUGCCGCAAUUUCCAUGCCAGGAUAUUUUUCCGCAAAUCAGUCGGUUGAAAUUCAGAGGAGUCAGAAUGACUCGACCUGUCCUUCAAUGUUGAUAAUAAAUGUCUCAGCCAAAAACCUUCCUUGAGCUGCCAUGCUUUUCCCCUUGACCUGCACCUCUUCCCCUAAAACUUCUGCAGGGAAGCCCCUGGCGGAGGCGCCAUUGAAAGCAUGGUCUUGCCAGUGGCUGGCAAGGCGGUUUUGUUCUGCUCAGUUUCUGGAGAGGGUUGGAUGCGUCCCCUGCCAUCCAGCCCUCCCCGCUUGAGGCCAGCACUGAGUCUGGGACACUCAGCGGGAAGGGGGCUGGCAUCGCCAGCGACCCACACAUUCCUCACGUAGCUUCUGCUCCCAGGAAGGUAGUUUAAAUCCUGUAUAUACUUUUUAGAGACUCUUUUAAACUUUCUGAAGUGCUGAUGUACAUACUUUCUCGUACACACUUUUGUGAAGAUUUCAAGGGGAAGGGAGUCGUCUGCCAUUCAAUGUUUACAUUUAUGUUCUGCAAGACGCUGUCCUCAGGGACCAUUAGGGGACCAUUCUGUUCAGUGCGAUCCUGAUGGUCCGGGAGAUGAGGGUUUCCGGGGCUAGUGAUCGUGAUCCCUUUUAUUUGCAACUGUAAUGAGAAUUUUUCACACUAACACAGCGAGGGACUCAACACGCUGAUUCUCCUCCUGCCUCUCCCGUGAGUCUCCAGCCUGCCCAGCACCGGCAGCUGUGGAGCACGUGGAUGCUGCCUACCCCGGCGCCCGCGUCUUCCACGGGCACAGGUGUGUGGAGGCCGUGGUCGGACCCUGGUGUCCUGGUUACUGCUGCCCGGGUGUCUUUUUUUUGAGUAACUGCUCUCUGAGUUUUGCACACGAAGUUGCCCUCAUCUGCUGGAGAUCGAUAAGGAAGGCACAAGACGUUCUCCUCUGCCCGUGAGGAGCUUCCCGCAGCCGCCUGGCCCAGCCUGGGCACGUUCUCCGAGGCAUGUGUCUCCCUGCUCACCCUCGUCUGGGCACCUCAGCAUCUGUGGACUUGAGCGUCCAAAAACCCUGAGUGUGAUUCUGGGCAGCCGGCCUGGCUUGAAGUCCGCCAUGACCCUGGGCACAGGGGAAGCCCAGCCGUGGGCUUAGGAGAGAGGGACCAGCGCCCAGCGUUAGGGCUGGAAGACGGCAGUGUUCAGAAUUCCAGCCGCUCAUCUGAACACAGAAGGUGUGAACUGACCUCUAAAGCAGCGUGAGAUGGGAAUGAUCUAGAAAACUUUGGAUUUUUGAAGUAAAUUUUAAUGUUUCAUAUUAAUUUCUUGAAAAUGUAUUAAAUGUCAUUGAAAGCCUUAUUACGCUUUUCAGAUCCUUUCAAUAAACAAGACUUGUAGAAAAUAA